AAGUGAGAGCCAUUGCAGAUAGCCAGUUUUCUUUAUUUUUAAUUGUUGUUUGUGCAAAAGGUUUUGGCGAAUACUGGCUAUAUUCAGAGGACUCAGUACCAGUUGCCAGGGGCCUGGAGUAGGUGCUGUGGUCUCAAUGUGUGUGUCCCCCCAAACCAUAUGUUGACACCUAACCCCCAAGGCGAUGUGGUUAGGAGAUGGAGCUUUAAGGAGGUGACUGGGCCGUGAGGGCUGUCCUCUCAUGACGGACGAGUGCCCUUCAACGAGACUUGAAGGAGCCCUUCUGUCCCUUCCUCCACGUGAGGACACAUAGAAGGUACCAUCUCUGGGGAACAGGCUGUCACCAAACACCAAGUCUGCUGGCGCCUGGAUCCUGGACUUCUCAGCCUCUACAACUGUGUGCAAUACAUUUCUACUGUUUAUCAAUCACAUGGUCAGAGGUAUUUUGUUACAGCAGCACAAAUGGACCAAGACAUCAGGUCUCCAAAUCGAAGAACUUCUCAGCAGCCUUCAGUGCUGGGUGGGGAGACAGAGGUUCCCUGCAGGUCCCCACAGACAGUGUUAGACUCAGUGCUGGGUGGGGAGACAGAGGUUCCCUGCAGGUCCGCACGGACGGUGUUAGACUCGGUGCUGGGUGGGGAGACAGAGGUUCCCUGCAGGUCCGCACGGACGGUGUUAGACUCGGUGCUGGGUGGGGAGACAGAGGUUCCCUGCAGGUCCGCACGGACGGUGUUAGACUCGGUGCUGGGUGGGGAGACAGAGGUUCCCUGCAGGUCCCCACGGACAGUGUUAGACUCGGUGCUGGGUGGGGAGGUUCCCAGCAGGUCCGCACGGACGGUGUUAGACUCGGUGCUGGGUGGGGAGGUUCCCUGCAGGUCCGCACGGACGGUGUUAGACUCGGUGCUGGGUGGGUUGACAGAGGUUCCCUGCAGGUCCGCACGGACGGUGUUAGACUGGGUGCUGGGUGGGGAGGUUCCCUGCAGGUCCGCACGGACGGUGUUAAACUCGGUGCUGGGUGGGGAGGUUCCCUGCAGGUCCGCACGGACGGUGUUAGACUCGGUGCUGGGUGGGGAGACAGGUUCCCUGCAGGUCCCCACAGACAGUGUUAGACUCGGUGCUGGGUGGGGAGGUUCCCUGCAGGUCCGCACGGACGGUGUUAGACUCGGUGCUGGGUGGGGAGACAGAGGUUCCCUGCAGGUCCCCACAGACAGUGUUAGACUCGGUGCUGGGUGGGGAGGUUCCCUGCAGGUCCGCACGGACGGUGUUAGACUCGGUGCUGGGUGGGGAGACAGAGGUUCCCUGCAGGUCCGCACGGACGGUGUUAGACUCAGUGCUGGGUGGGGAGACAGAGGUUCCCUGCAGGUCCGCACAGAUGGUGUUAGACUCGGUGCUGGGUGGGGAGACAGAGGUUCCCUGCAGGUCCGCACGGACGGUGUUAGACUUGGGGGACACUGGGUCCCCAGUAAGAAUGAUUCUGAUGUGAGUGCAGCUAGUGAGGGCUGAGUUCAAGCUUUAAAGACAAGAGCCCAACAGGUUCCUUCAACAGCCUGAUCCCCUAGACCUUCGUGUGUCCAAGUCUCCAGAGGGGAUGAACCUCAACAGACCUGGUUCGACCUCCCCUAGGCAGUGGGUGCUGCCUGGAGGGCAGGGUCGCUCGAGACUGUAGGAGACUCUGCACGUGGUGACCAUAGCACCCCCAUAAUAAAGCAGCCCGUGAGGGCAGCCUGGCUGUUCGGCGAUGUGUGCACUGAGGUCAUCUCUCCUACUCUGUCUCAGCUAUUUAAAGGCUGUGACUCACCAUGUGGAUUUAAUGACUUAUUAAGGAGUUGCAGCCCAUGCUUUUUAAAAAAGUAAUCUACAAAAAAAUAAAUGAAAAAGUCUUCAGGACAGUAGACUUAAGUGCGGAUGUGGUCCCUCGAGUUCCAUUUUUCAGCCGCCCACAUUCCUGGGAUUCAGACCUGUUGGGGAUUGUAGGAUUCUAGUUGCACAGGGAAACCCAGAGUCAAUUCAGGAGGAUAAUUCUGAGCCAGGGGUGGGGGUACCGGCCUGGAGCUCCGGGGGGUACGGGCUGAUCCUACGAAAGGAAAGUCAAGCCUGUGAAUUGCAGAGCCUGGACAGAGAAGUUGAGGUGACGGCGUUCUGCAGAUCCGUGAAAUUCUAUUACACGUCAGAGGGAAGGGACGGCCUCAUGUGGCCCCUUGGAGGGACCAAGCCCUACCCAGCGCCUUGCCCAAGUCAGCACGCAGUCAGUGUUGGCUCCACCCACCUGCACCGUCAGGCCUUCUGGAAAGAGAAGGAGAUCCGACUGACGGAGCGUCUCCAAACUUCCAAGCAAAUAUUACCUCGUUAAAGCCCAGUGCCACAUGACUGACCUGGAGCCACAGCCUGCCCUCCUUCCCUGGGCCUACAGGAAGGGGGAGGUUCCUGUCACCAGAACCGUUCCGUCAUCAGCCGGGCAGAUGCUCGCUGUGGAUUCUAGGUGAGCAUCAAGUACUAGGGACCAUGUUUGUCUUGGAUUCCCCCGUCCCGCCUGAGCCCAGAACGCAGAGCCGGAGUCAGGGGCUUGCACAUGGAGCGUUUCACGCCCAGGAGGCUGGGGCAGGGGCCAGGAAGGAGCGGGGAGGGGGCCAGGACCAGCGUGCUCUGCUGAGGGUCCACAUCGAGGGCUGGACCCUGGACCUCCACAAGCCUGGAGAAUUCUCCAUCCGAGCAGUGAGGAGCCCCUGCUUGUUGUCAGCUGGAGCUGCGCCUCGGGGCUUCUGCUGUCCUGGCCCUGGGGUGGUGACUGCAGGAUCCCACAGGUGUCCCGAGGCCUGAGGCUCUUCUCACUGCAGAGGCCACCCUGCAGGAAUUGGAGUUAGGACCCGGAGGGUGGGACAGGCUGACUCAGAGGAGCCAGCUCUCAGGUUGGCAGGAGGAGGAGAUGCACAAUGAGACGGCAGCCUCACCUCCAGGGGACGGCCCCGCAAGCCGGAGCUGCCCUCCUGCACACUCAGCACUCAAGGUGGAUUUGGAGGUGACCUAAGCCCACAGCUCUCCAAGUCUUGGGGAAAUCUACAGUGGAUGGCAGGUGCCUGCGGACGCCGAGUGGGUGCGGCCCCAGUUAUGCUCAAUGCAGGGGCACCUGUGUUGUUAGCAGCUGACGUGGACGGGAAAGGCCUGUGCUGAACAACGUUCCGUGUUCAAUUAGACACUCUCCUCCUAAACAGGGGCGGAAGACGUCUCAUGGGGGUUCCAAGCGUGAUUUAUGGAACUCACUCCCAUGAGAUAACAUAACAUUUUUCACACGUGGGAGAAAGGGCUGGGCUCGACUGGUGCCUGAGUGAAUGCUGAGGAUAAAUGGGAAGCAGGACAUUCCAGGGCACCUCUGCGUCUUGCAUGAGACCUUGUGAGGGCCCUGUGGUGCCCCUGAUGUCACUGUCGAAGGUGGAGCCGCCCCCGCUCUGCCUCGGCCUCCCUCAGAUGUCCUCCCCAGCUGGCCCUGCAGCGCACGUGGAAGACAGCUGCCGAGAAGCAGGUGUGAUGCCAGCCUGUGGGAGAAGCCACAUCUGGACAGUGCGUGAAGCCAGUCCAGGGGCCACACCGGGACCUGCCCUCAGCUCUGCCACGUCCUGGCCAAGUGGCCUUGGCAUGCCAGCCCUGGUGUCCACAGAGGCAUCCAUUCCUCAUGGCAAAGUGGAGUCAAGUCGGCUGAUGCAGGCGAGACACCUGGCCGGCCUGGGGAGCCGCACCAGCGCUCCCCACAUUGCACUGCUGACUGAGGGGUGCUCGGUGCCGCGGCUUCACACGGUCAGUGCACAGACAUGAACGCUGGACUGAGAAGCCGCCGCGUGCACCUGGCCCGCCAAGUUGCCAGGGAGGCAAGGGUGGUGUUGACGUGGAUCACCGAAGGAGCUGGCAGCCCAGCCGUCCCCGUGACUGGAUGGAAUCCGCAAGCGUUCCUGGGCAUCCACUCUGGGAAGGGCUCAGUGCCAGGGCCUAGGGUAGUUUUCAAAUUGCAGGUUGUGGCCAGUAUACCAGGGGUCAUGGGGUCAGUACACUGGGCUCUGACUGGCAAUUCCUAAAGAUGAAGUGUGAGUCUGUCCCAUAUAGUAAGAGCUGCAUUGAUUUGUAAAGCUUGUGUUGGUUUUGCACGUUCUAUGCCAGUGUGUGCUGGACCGUGAUAGAAAGCGCAUUUCUCGCUGUGGUGCCUGCCGUAGUCUGGAGGGAAAGAUGAGUCCGUGGCUCUAAUGUGGGGUGGUGGGUGUGGUCUACACAGGGAGAGCGAAGAGCCCACAUGGGGCAUGAGAGGGGCCGGAGAGGCUGGGGCAGGGGAACCCGGGCCAGGUCCUGAGAACAAAUGGGGUUAUUCAGCUCCUAAAGGUGCAGGACUCAGCCCAAAGUCCCUGGUGACCCAAAGAGGACCAUGUGAGUCUGAUGUGGCUGUGGAAGGCGGGGCUCACAGCAGGCUGCCGGGGCACCAUUAAUGGGGGAGGGUCCUGUCCCCAGCGCAUACGUAGACGGCCCUUCAGAACCUGCUCAGUGGUCAGUGCGGCCGUGCAGCUGCACCCCGGCCUGGUCACCUGUGCUGUGCCCAGCAAGGAAGAUGCCCCCGCUCAGCCCGUCCAUGCACCCUCCAGAGGCUGUUAGCUGCCUGAGACCCACACUGGCUCUUGCAGGCUAGAGGAGAGUUCAAUGGCCAUUCGGGCCCUGUCGCCAUGGAAACACCAACUUUGGGUACCAAAAGCCUGAAUGUACAAAUUCAUGGAGUAUGACCUGCCUGGUGCCAGUGGGUCUUUGCAUUUUUCUGGGGUGCCAGUGGGUCUUUGCGUUUUUCUGGGGUGCCAGUGGGUCUUUGCGUUUUUCUGAUGCCCUCUGAACUCUUAGGUCCCGGUUCUGGCGGAUUUGGCCCAGGCACCCCCAGCCCCCAGAUCUGGCCGGGUGCGGCGGCUCAUGCCUGUAAUCCCAGCACUUUGGGAGGCCGAAGCAGGUGGAUCACAUGAAGUCAGAAGUUGGAGACUAGCCUGGCCAACAUGCCAGCCUCCAGCAUCGCCUCCUCUGGGAUCUUCUCUGACUUCCCAGUCGGUUUCAGAAGCCUCUGAUGACCCCAUGCGGAGAAGACUGCUCCCCUCACUGCUGGCACACGGCAGAUGCUCAGUAAGUAUCGUUCAAUGACUGACUAAAUGUCUCAUAAUAUCCUUCAUAAACAAGGGCCUGGUGUGGAUUCAUAAAUGGGUCUCUCAAAGUUUAAUUGGUGAGACUCUGUUGUAUCAGACAAUGAAGGGUUAAAAGAUAAUAUUCAAAAAAGUAAAAUCAUGACACACAAAUCUAGAAUGAACACACAUUGAUAAGGUUUGGAUCUGUGUCCUCACCCAAACCUCAUGUCGAACUGGGAUCCCCCGUGUCAGAGGCGGCCGCGUGGGAGGUGACCGGAUCGCGGGUGGACCCUUCAUGAAGGGUUCAGCACCAUCCCCUUGGUGCUGUCCUGGGACAGAGUUCUCUUGCGAUCUGGUUGUUUAAACGUGUGUGGCCCCUUCCCCCUCUCUUUUCCUCCUCCUCCUGCCGUGGGAGACACUUGCUCCAGCUUCGCCUUCCGCCGCGAGUUGAAGCUCCCCGAGGCCUCCUCAGAAGCAGAAGCCACCACGCUUCCUGUACAGCCUGUGGGACCCGGAGCCAGUUCAACCUCUUUUCUUUAUAAAUUACCCAGACUCGGCCGGGCACGGUGGCUCACGCCUGUAAUCCCAGCACUUUGUUGAGACCGAGGCAGGCAGAUCACGAGGUCAGGAGAUCGAGAACAUCCUGGCUAACACGGUGAAACCCCGUCUCUACUAAAAAUACAAAAAAUUAGCCGGGCGUGGUGGCGGGCGCCUGUGGUCCCAGCUACUCGGGAGGCUGAGGCAGGAGAAUGGUGUGAACCCGGGAGGCGGAGCUUGCAGUGAGCCGAGAUCCCGCCACUGCACUCCAGCCUGGGCAGCAGAGCGAGACUCCAUCUCAACAAAUAAUAAUAAUAAAAUAAAUAAAUAAAUAAAUAAAUAAA